AGCCGGCCUUCCGAGGCCCUAGGUAUUCCGCGCACCAAAGAAGGUGCUGAAGUUAUGGGGCUGGGGUUAUUAUUAUCAUUGACCAAAGCAAAGGACUUUCCAUUAAUUUCUCGUUAAUUUAUUGUUAAUUUCUCACACGAGCUCGGCAAGAGAGGCUUUACUAUUCCCAGAGAAUCCGAGAUUCAGAAAAAGCGAAGGAAACUGCAUAAGGCCUCAUAGCUAGGAAGCGGCACCGUUGGAAUGUGGACUCAGAAGUCUGGUCCCAAGCCGACAGAACAGAUCACUGCCCAGAACAGAAAAGUUAGAAGUGGAACCGGUGUGCAGAAUUUCUAGAAUUUGGAAUCGAGUGCAUUUUCUGACAUUUGAGUACAGUACCCAGGGGUUCUUGGAGAAGAACCUGGUCCCAGAGGAGCUUGACUGACCAUAAAAAUGAGUACUGCAGAUGCACUUGAUGAUGAAAACACAUUUAAAAUAUUAGUUGCAACAGAUAUUCAUCUUGGAUUUAUGGAGAAAGAUGCAGUCAGAGGAAAUGAUACGUUUGUAACACUCGAUGAAAUUUUAAGACUUGCCCAGGAAAAUGAAGUGGAUUUUAUUUUGUUAGGUGGUGAUCUUUUUCAUGAAAAUAAGCCCUCAAGGAAAACAUUACAUACCUGCCUCGAGUUAUUAAGAAAAUAUUGUAUGGGUGAUCGGCCUGUCCAGUUUGAAAUUCUCAGUGAUCAGUCAGUCAACUUUGGUUUUAGUAAGUUUCCAUGGGUGAACUAUCAAGAUGGCAACCUCAACAUUUCAAUUCCAGUGUUUAGUAUUCAUGGCAAUCAUGACGAUCCCACAGGGGCAGAUGCACUUUGUGCCUUGGACAUUUUAAGUUGUGCUGGAUUUGUAAAUCACUUUGGACGUUCAAUGUCUGUGGAGAAGAUAGACAUUAGUCCGGUUUUGCUUCAAAAAGGAAGCACAAAGAUUGCGCUAUAUGGUUUAGGAUCCAUUCCAGAUGAAAGGCUCUAUCGAAUGUUUGUCAAUAAAAAAGUAACAAUGUUGAGACCAAAGGAAGAUGAGAACUCUUGGUUUAACUUAUUUGUGAUUCAUCAGAACAGGAGUAAACAUGGAAGUACUAACUUCAUUCCAGAACAAUUUUUGGAUGACUUCAUUGAUCUUGUUAUCUGGGGCCAUGAACAUGAGUGUAAAAUAGCUCCAACCAAAAAUGAACAACAGCUGUUUUAUAUCUCACAACCUGGAAGCUCAGUGGUUACUUCUCUUUCCCCAGGAGAAGCUGUAAAGAAACAUGUUGGUUUGCUGCGUAUUAAAGGGAGGAAGAUGAAUAUGCAUAAAAUUCCUCUUCACACAGUGCGGCAGUUUUUCAUGGAGGAUAUUGUUCUAGCUAAUCAUCCAGACAUUUUUAACCCAGAUAAUCCUAAAGUAACCCAAGCCAUACAAAGCUUCUGUUUGGAGAAGAUUGAAGAAAUGCUUGAAAAUGCUGAACGGGAACGUCUGGGUAAUUCUCACCAGCCAGAGAAGCCUCUUGUACGACUGCGAGUGGACUAUAGUGGAGGUUUUGAACCUUUCAGUGUUCUUCGCUUUAGCCAGAAAUUUGUGGAUCGGGUAGCUAAUCCAAAAGACAUUAUCCAUUUUUUCAGGCAUAGAGAACAAAAGGAAAAAACAGGAGAAGAGAUCAACUUUGGGAAACUUAUCACAAAGCCUUCAGAAGGAACAACUUUAAGGGUAGAAGAUCUUGUAAAACAGUACUUUCAAACCGCAGAGAAGAAUGUGCAGCUCUCACUGCUAACAGAAAGAGGGAUGGGUGAAGCAGUACAAGAAUUUGUGGACAAGGAGGAGAAAGAUGCCAUUGAGGAAUUAGUGAAAUACCAGUUGGAAAAAACACAGCGAUUUCUUAAAGAACGUCAUAUUGAUGCCCUCGAAGACAAAAUCGAUGAGGAGGUACGUCGUUUCAGAGAAACCAGACAAAAAAAUACUAAUGAAGAAGAUGAUGAAGUCCGUGAGGCUAUGACCAGGGCCAGAGCACUCAGAUCUCAGUCAGAGGAGUCUGCUUCUGCCUUUAGUGCUGAUGACCUUAUGAGUAUAGAUUUAGCAGAACAGAUGGCUAAUGACUCUGAUGAUAGCAUCUCAGCAGCAACCAACAAAGGAAGAGGCCGAGGAAGAGGUCGAAGAGGUGGAAGAGGGCAGAAUUCAGCAUCGAGAGGAGGGUCUCAAAGAGGAAGAGCAGACACUGGUCUGGAGACUUCUACCCGUAGCAGGAACUCAAAGACUGCUGUGUCAGCAUCUAGAAAUAUGUCUAUUAUAGAUGCCUUUAAAUCUACAAGACAGCAGCCUUCCCGAAAUGUCACUACUAAGAAUUAUUCAGAGGUGAUUGAGGUAGAUGAAUCAGAUGUGGAAGAAGACAUUUUUCCUACCACUUCAAAGACAGAUCAAAGGUGGUCCAGCACAUCAUCCAGCAAAAUCAUGUCCCAGAGUCAAGUAUCGAAAGGGGUUGAUUUUGAAUCAAGUGAGGAUGAUGAUGAUGAUCCUUUUAUGAACACUAGUUCUUUAAGAAGAAAUAGAAGAUAAUAUAUUUAAUGGCACUGAGAAACAUGCAAGAUACAGGAAAAAUGAAAAUGUUACAAGCUAAGAGUUUACAGUUUAAGAUUUUAAGUAUUGUUUCCUGAGCAUAACUCCAUAAGUAAGAAAUUUCUAGUUCACAGACAUACAAUAGCAUUGAUUCACCUUGUUUUUUUAACCUGGUUGUUGUAGUAAGAGCUUUGUUUCAAUAUCACUCUUGAGUAAAGAUUAAAAUAAAGCUACCAUUUUACAUUUCUAUUUCAUAAUGAAAAACUAUGUCAGUAUUUUAAUAUGGUUACAUUUAGCCAAAGUUGAGGGAAAGAGCUUAUAAAAUUUAACUUCUUCAUAAUUUUAGUAAUUUCCUAGAGGUUCUGGGUUUUCUGAAAGUAAAACAAUUUAUGCGAACCUAUGUCUAAAUUCACUGUUUGUUACUAUGUAUGUUUUUUUCCAAUGCUUCUUAUAAGACUAAAUGAUUAGAAGUACCUAAUAGUUUGAACAGAUAUGUUUUUAUUUAAAAGAGUAGAAUAACCUUUCAGAAUUACUGAGUUUUUUAUUCCAGUUGUAGCAAAGAUUUCAAAAGAUUGUGUUCCCAUUAAGUGGUAGUAAUUUCCUUUAUUAUUCUGUAUCCUUAAUGGUGUUCUCUCUCUCUCUCUCUCUCUCUCUCUCUCCCUCUCCCCCCCGUUCCCCACUCUUCCUUUCUCCUUUGCUUUUUCUUCUCUUUCAUACAUAUAUGCGUGCCUAGUUCUAGGAGGAAACGGGUUAAAAAUUGUUUUAAACUACAUCUUGAAAAUAUUGAAGAAUUUGUUUUAGGUAGAGUGGUCAGUUGAACCUUACAGUAAAGUAUAGAAAUAUAUUUAAUGUGGAAUGUCAAUGCCAGGAUUUCUCAUUAACAAUAUUUUAUCUCAACUUUGGUUCCUGUGAUACAUUUCUGAAUGGGCAAUUCCAGAAAUCUUAGUAGCCCAUGUUAAGCUUCUAUUUUUUACUUGUUUUCGGGGAGAAAUAAGAAUUAGACAUCUUCAGAUUUAAGUUAAAUAAUCCCAUUCUUUAUAAUCCUCUGUAAAAAGAUCCCUGAGAUUAUUCCUUCUUCUAGUUUUAUGCGACAGCUUUACUUUAAAAUUCAAGUUAUACAUCUUGGGAGUACAAUGGCCCGACAUUUCUUCAUAGGUAGAAACAAAUACUUGACUCAGUGAUACUCAUGACCAUUAGAAUAGUCAUACCUGGAAUGUGUCAAAUUAUAAGAGACAGACACUUGGUUAGUGGCUGCCUCAUAUAGCACUUUUGAAGAGGCCUAAGUCAAAACUUGCAAUAUAACAUUCUAUUGACUUUCUUAAAAAUAUUUUUUCUGUACCUAACUUGAGCAUAAGGGUUAUUUGAGCAAGUAACAUUAACUCAGUGGAAGGCAUUGUCCUGUGAAAUAUUCUUAGGCAGAUCUGCCCACAUCUUUAUUGAACUUGAAAUCUAAUAUUUCUAGUAUUUGAACAAAGCAGAAGGUUAAGUCAGGGAAGAGCAGUGCUGUCCAUGAUGUAAUGGAAGCUACCAGGGGAGGCAGUGUCUGGAUGAUGCUGUGCUACCUACCCCUGCACAAGCCAUGCUGGCUCAGUCUGAGCUGUGGGCCACAUCAGCUAGUGGCUCUUCUCAUGCAUCAGUUAGGUGGGUCUGGGUGAGAGUUAUAGUGAGGGAAUGGUCACUAAAGUAUCCUGACAAGUUCCUAGGAAAAAAGGAAUAAAGUUUUUUUCCUUAAAAAAAAAAAAAUUGCUCUUGGCUGUGAAAAGAGGUACUAAAUGCGAUUCAGUUCACCGCUAAGGAAAGUGAUGACAUAGCAGUUACAGAGGGUGAUAAAUCUCUCCAGCUAAUUCAGGUCAUUUUGUGAAUACUAUGUAUCAAGCCCUGAAAAUAUGGUAAAUAAAACGUGACAGGGAAACCUUUUUUUGAUUGAAUAUUGUUACAUAGUUAAAUGUGCUAUAUAUCCUUAAUAUUUUAUAUUGAUCCUGCAAAAUCUGUUGGUUUUAGGGGAGUUUUGUUUUUUGUUUCUAACAAUUUUCAGACCUGUUGGUAUAGGAAUGUAGAAGUCUUUCAGAUGAUUUGAAAGCAGCUGCAUUUGCUCUUGGAGGCUUUGGGAGAGCAGGAAUGAAAACAUUCAGAGGAAGACAUCUGUAGGGAAUUCUUCUGUUACUUACCAAAGAAUAAGUGUCUUUCUGGUGUUUUAUUUCCUAUCAUAAAAAUACAACAGUGCAUUUACAAGGUUAAAGAUUCCUCGAAGUUCUAGGAAAUUCUUGAAAAUAUAAGUGGUGCUUAGAAAAUUCAAGCAUUUAGGAAUGUGACCUUUAAUUCAGGUAUGUAAAAGACUUUUUUCCCAAACUUUUAAAAGUAGGAAAUACAAUAAAUACAGAAAAGUCAUAUGGUUGAAUAAAUAAUUAUAAAUUGAGCACUGAUGGAAUCCCUCUACAGGUCAAGAAAUAGCGCAGUGUCCUGGAUGCCCAUUAUAUUGUUUUCUCCUUUCUGGGUAACAAGCCCUAACUUCUGUAAUUUAAAAGCUCCUACUUUUGCCACAAGGUGGUGCUUCUGCCAUUAGACGCAGUUAGGAGGAUGCAACUGCAAAUCUAAAAUUACGAAGUUAGUGUAGUUGCAAUAAACUUAGAACAUAUGCAUUAAUACUAAACCUAUGCAGUAAUACCAUAAUUAGCCUUCUAAUCAUGUAAUUUGCUUUACUUAGGUAUUUCAUUUGGUUCAGCCUGUUAUGGAAUUUACCAGCUUGAUAAAUUUGCCUAUAAAGUUUUAUAAAGAAAAGGAAUAUUUUGUUUUCAUAAAGAGGAAAAUCCAUUCUUAGAAAAAAACUGAGUAAAAAAGUAUCUCAAUGGGCUGGGUGCAGUGGCUCAUGCCUUUAAUCCCAGCACUUUGGGAGGCCGAGGAGGGGGUUCACCUGAGGUCAGGAGUUUGAGACCAGCCUGGCCAACAUGGUGAAACCUCGUCUCUACUAAAAAUACAAAAGAUUAGCUGGGCAUGGUGGUGUGUGCCUGUAAUCUUAGCUACUCAGGAGGCUGAGGCAGGAGAAUCGCUUGAACCCAGGAGGCAGAGGUUGCAGUGAGCCGAGAUUGUGCCAUUGCACUGCAGCCUGGGCAACAAGAGUGAAACUCAAUCUCAAAAAAAAAAAAAGUAUCUAAAUGUAAAAUAUCUUUUUUGGAAAUAUAGAAUUUAAAAGCGACUUUCCCCCAAAGAAAUCUGAUGUCCUUUUUGUAUCUGUCAUAAAUUUAAUUCAUAGUAUUUUGGGUUUUUUUUGUUUUUUUUUUUUGAGACGGAGUCUCGCACUCUUGCCCAGGCUGGAGGGCAGGGGCACCAUUUCGGCUCACUGCAAGCUCCACGCCAUUCUCCUGCCUCAGCCUCCCAAGUAGCUGGGACUACAGGCGCCCACCACCACGCCUGGCUAAUUUUUUUUUUUUUUUUUUUGUAUUUUUAGUAGAGACAGGGUUUUUCUGUGUUAGCCAGGAUGGUCUCGAUCUCCUGACCUUGUGAUCCACCCACCUCAGCCUCCCAAAGUGCUGGGAUUACAGGCCUGAGCCACCACGCCCAGCCUAUUUUGUGUUUUUUUAAAGCUAACUACCAUUAAGAUCAUUAUAGAAGUUUGGUAUAAUGAAGAUUUGGGUUUUUCAGUCCAAUGAGUUUCCAUAUUCUUGAAUGAAAAAGAUCCACAUUUCAUCAUUUGCCUGUUUCAUUUUCUUUUAGUACUUUUGAACUUAGUUUGGUCAGAAAAUACUAGAAUUUUAGUUUGAUCUAAAGAACCAGCUUAUAUAACUUGCUGUUGCCAUGUACAUUUGUAUGUCUUUGCUGUGUCAAAUAACUGGAUCUGAUUUUAGCUCUUUUUAAGUGGUGAAAGCAAUGCAUUUUUAUUCUUCAAAUUCAGACAUUGAAUGUGUAUUAAAAUGUGUGUGCUUACCUUUAAUCCUCUCCCCACCGACAAUUAGGAACACGUUUCUCCAAUUACUGUUGGCAAGACUACCAAGAAAAAUUGUUGAAUUAGAAUCCCAGCACCGGGCACGGUGGCUCACGCCUGUGAUCCUAGCACUUUGGGAGGCCAAAGCAGGCGGAUCACCUGAGGUCAGGAGUUCGAGACCAGCAGGGCCAACAUGGCGAAACCCCGACUCUACUAAAAAUACAAAAAUUAGCCAGGCAUGGUGGUGGGCGCCUGUAAUCCCAACUACUCAGGAGGCUGAGGCAGGAGAAUUGCUUGAACCUGGGAGUUGGAGGUCACGGUGAGCUGAUAUCACGCCAUUGCACUCCAGCCUGGGCAACAGAGCAAGACUCUGUCUCAAUCAAUCUAUCCAUCAAUCGAUAAGAACCCCAGAUUGUAUAGCUACAUGUUUUAGCCCCCUUUUCAAAGUAUAUGUUCUCCUUGGUACUUAUUUUGACAUUCUGACUUUUCUACAUAUGCUUUAUCAACCUCUUAAUUAAACCAUCAUUGUCUAUUUUGAGAGAUAACUGCGCUGCUUCCCGUUGUGUGUUUUAAAUGUUAUUGUUCAGUUUGAGUCAAAUAAAAGGAUAUUUAAUCUGUGGUGCCUUGACAUUAAAA